UUAGUUCUGUUUGAAAAAUUAACUUUAAAGACAAGAACAUAAUUAUGAAUGCAUACUUUAUUCAAAUAUUAGCAUUUUAAGUAAAAUUUAUUUUCUUCACAAUUAGAAAACAUGAAAAGGCAUAUACAAUGCCUUUGGUGUUUUGAAUUUAAGAAUCAAUGUCUGAGGGACUUUUGUGUGUGAAAAUAAAUAUUCAUGGCCGGGCGCGGUGGCUCACGCCUGUAAUCCUAGCACUUUGGGAGGCCGAGGCGGGUGGAUCACGAGGUCAGGAGAUCGAGACCAUCCUGGCUAACAUGGUGAAACCCCGUCUCUACUAAAAAUACAAAAAAUUAGCCGGGUGUGGUGGCGGGCACCUGUAGUCCCAGCUACUCGGGAGGCUGAGGCAAGAGAAUGGCAUGAACCAGGGAGGCAGAGCUUGCAGUGAGCCGAGAUCGUGCCACUGCACUCCAGCCUGGGCGACAGAGCCAGACUCUGCUUAAAAAAUAAAUAAAUAAAUAAAUAUUCAUACACAUUUUUCGUUGUUUAAUGUUUGAUGUAUUACACUGCUUUCUAUUAAACAAAACUUUAAAAACUGAUUUUCUUGUGUAUCUAAAUCUGGGUUAUAAAUUUGGUUAGCUUAACUCCCGUAACAAAUAUAGUGUUUAUUUAUAACUUGUAUUUGGUUGAUUCUUUUGGAAAACUUGGAAUACAAUAACAUUUAGACAAAAUAUUUAUAAAUACAAUGAUUACAAAAUAUGUUAACCUUAUAUCACAUCCAGUUAAAAACGUGCUGAUAAUAUGGAUUUAAUUUCUUAGUCAAGUCACAAGGGCUGGGUGGUCUCUCAUCUCGAUGGCUCCCGGUGAGCCCUGGAACAUGGCGGUGUGGUCCAAGGCGAUUUAAACCUGUGCCGCAGAUUAUUCAGCUGAGUCCUUUUUGCAAUAGAGAUUUAAGACCCUCUUUCAUUUAAAUUUAAAUUUUUGAAACUUAGUGUCAAAUGCUAAAAUAUCAUUGGAACAUUACUUUAGAUUAGAAAAUAUUUUAUUAAUAAUUCAGACAGAGUGUGAUAUGGUUUGGCUGUGUCCCCCCCAAAUCUCAUCUUGAAUUGUAGUUCCCAUAAUCCCCACAUGUUACCCAGUGGGAGGUAAUUGAAUCAUGGGGGCGGUUAGCCCAUGCUGCUAUUCUCAUGAUAGUGAGUGAGUUCUCAUGAGAUCUGAUGGUUUUAUCCAGGACUUUUCCCCCUUUUGCUCAGCACCUCUCCUUGCUGCUGCCAUGUGAAGAAGGAUGUGUUUGCUUCCCGUUCCGCCAUGAUUGUAAGUUUCCUGAGGCCUCCCCGAACUAUGAGUCAAUUAAAUCUCUUUCGUUUAUAAAUAGCCGAGCACUGUGAGAAUGGACUAAUAAAUACGAGUGUCUUAAUCCAUUUUGCAUUGUUAUAAAGGAAUAUCUGAGGCUGGGUAAUUUAAUAAAAUAAGACAUUUAUUUGACUCACGGUUCUUCAGGCUCUGCAAGAAGCAUGGCACCAGCAUCUGCUUCUGGUGAGGACCUCAUGAAGUUUCUAACCAUGGGGGGAGGCCAAGAGAGAGCAGGCAUGUCACAUGGCAAGGGAGGGAGCAAGAGAGAGGGGAGGAGUGCCAUGCUCUUUUAGGCAGCCAGAUCCCACAGGAACUAAGAGUGAGAAUUCACUCAAUCCUAACAUAAUGACACCAAGCAACUCAUGAGGGAUCUGCCCCCCUGACCCAAACACCUCCAACUAGGCCCCACCUCCCACAUUAGGGAUGAAAUUUCAACAUGAUAUUUGGAGGGAACUAAUAUCCAAACUAUGUCAUAGAGGUAUGUGUGUAACCUCAUUCAUUUAUGCAUUCAUUCAACAAAAUAUGUAGUGAGCACCUGCUAUGUGCCAGGCACUGUGCUAGGCUGUAGAUAUGACUCAUAAAUAAGAUUAAUAUUGCCACAGUCCUUAGGAGCCUAGUGUAGUUGGGGAGUAAAUAAGCAAACAGAUAAUUUCUAUACCUGGUAAUUACUACCUUGAUAGGGCAAAGAGGAUUCUGUUUGUGCUGUAAAAGCACAUGAAAAGUACAAAGUCAAUCCUUGGGAGGUCAUGGAAUCUUUCCUAGGAAAUGAUAUAUAAGGUGGAUAAAAAGGUAACCAGAUACAGAUGAGAAGAGAAGGUGGGCCAGAAAUUUUGAAAUACUGAACCAACUGGAUGUCAUUCACUGACAUAGGGUAAUAGUAUAGAUGACUGGAUUGGAAAAUGAAAAAGGAACUAAAAGUAAUUAAAUGAGCUGCAGACAUGAAAAUGAACACUUGGGAAGUCCUGGCAGGAAGUCAUCAAUAAGACAACAUAAUGAAGUGGAAAGUGGUUGGGAGUAAGGCUGACUUGGAUUCAAACCCUAGUUUCACCACUUAAUAGACGUGUUAAGUUGAACAAAUCCUUUAACUUUUCAGAGCCUCAAUUUUCCUCUUUGUAAAAUACAGAUAAUAACAUGGACACUAUAAGGGUUUUGUUGUUGUUGUUGUUGUUUUGAGACGGAGUCUUGCUCUGUUGCCCAGGCUGGAGUGCAGUGCCUCGAUCUUGGCUCACUGCAACCUCUGCCUCCUGGGUUCAAGCGAUUCUCCUGCCUCAGCUUCCAGAGUAGCUGGGACUACAGGCGCACGCCACCAUGCCUGGCUAAUUUUUGUAUUUUUUGUAGAGACGGGGUUUCACCAUAUUGGCCAGGCUGGUCUCGAACUCCUGAUCUCAGAUGAUCCGCCUGCCUUGGCCUCCCAAAGUGCUGGGAUUACAGGCGUGAGCCACCGCACCUGGCCCAGACACUGUAAGUUUUGGGGAGGAUUAAAUGGGAUCAUCCAUGUAAAUGCGCCUAUCCCAGUCUCUAGCACACACUGAACACUCAAAAAUGGGAGGUUUUGGUAUUUCAGAAGAAAAUCAGGUGUCGGGGAGUGUUAGUAGUAACCUUGAACUAUAUGCAAAGACUAAAGCUAGGAAGAUAGGAAGAGUUUUACAAGAUCCUUUUGGCUAUAUAGUUAAAGUUAUUAGCAGUUAGAGUUUCCCUUACAGUUGACAAGUGAACCAUACAAGUGAAUGACUUGUGGUUCCUCAGAUAAAAGCACGAGUCAGAGUUGUAAUUUCUGUUUUGUGGACGUAAUUGUUGACCAAGUGCACUGAAGGUAGGGAUGGCCAGUAACAAAAUUAUAAAGCAGGCCUGUUUGUCUUCAAACACUCCUGAGUAAACUUGUCAUUUCCUUGUAAAAAUGCAAAAUAGACUACUGAGUAGAGGUGAUCAAUUACAGAAAUGCACUUACUUUGGCUUUCUUCUGAAACCUAAUAAAAUGACAGUAAAGGGAUUAUUUUUUUAAGGCAGAAACCCACAAUGAUGAUGAAAUUAGAAAGGAAGACAAGAACAACAAGGUUGUGGAAUUCAGAAGCCAUAUAGACAAGAGGUAACACACCUGAGAAAGAUGAUCCCUAAAUUUGUCUUGGAGAAAACUCAGAAGUACCUGACUACAUCAUAGACCUCCCAAACAGCUUCCAAAUGUCAGAUACCACUGAAAAUGGGGAUAAAGGUAGGGUCAAAAAUAGGAGGAUUGGGUUAUAAGUCUGUAUAAGAAGUUGUUAGAUCCCUACAUCCUCUCUUCAAACCUGUAUAGCCAGAUAAUGGUCCCUCUCCCAGCCUGGCAGAGGCUGGAAAAGGUAAAUAGAGAAACUUACUUCCUGGAGAACAUUUGGCACAUUUGGGGAUGGAGUUCAGUAAUAUAAAUGAAGGGGUAGUGAAAAUUUAUGGGAACAUUUAUAAGCUAACAGAACCCCAUGUCUUUUACCCCAUUCUAAUUCCAGACCACUAGAGAUUAGAAAAUUAUUCUCUGGGGUAUCUGACCACUUCCAGAGGAAAGACAUAAAGAUGCUGAUGUCGAGAAUGACCCAACUAAAUGGCCCAGCCAGAUGACCCAGUUGAAGCUGGUGGACAAGAAGUUUCAUUCAUGGAAUCAGAACUUCCAAUAAGGUCUUUUAGUACCUCACUCCUAAAUUUGAAUAGACUACCAAAGAUUAUCAGACAUCUAAGGGGAACUACCAGCAUGAAAGGUAGAGACCAAAGCAAACAAACAAACAAAGAAAAUAAUUUGGAACUAACCAAGACUAUGCUGGGAGAAGAAAACUAUUAUUAAUAUCCACAGAGCGUAGUACAGCCACUAUGGAGAACAGUAUGGAGGUUCCUGUAAAGACUAAAAAUAGAACCAUCAUAUAAUUCAACAAUCCCACUGCUAGAUAUAUACCCCAAAGAAAGGAAAUCAGUAUAUUGAAAAGAUAUCUGCACUCUCAUGUUUACUGUAGCACUAUUCAUAAUAGCCAAGAUUUGGAAGCAACUUAAGUGUCCAUCAACAGAUGAAUAGAUUUUUUUAAAAUGUGGUACAUAUACACAAUGGAGUACUAUUCAGCCAUAAAAAAGAAUGAGAAAUGUCAUUUGCAACAACAUGGUUGGAACUGGAGGACCUUAUGUUAAGUGAAAUAAGCCAGGCCCAAAAAAACAAAUUUCACAUGUUCUCACUCAUUUGUGGGACCUAAAAAUGAAAACAGUUGAACUCAGGGAGAUAGAGUAGGAUGAUGGUUACCAGAGGCUGGAAGGGUAGUUGUGGUGGGAGGUGGGUGGUUAAUGAGUACAAAAAUAUAGUUAGAUAGAAUGAAUAAAUCUAAUAGUUGCUAGCACAACAGGGUGACUACAGUCAACAAUAAUUUACCAUACAUUUAAAAUAACUAAAAGAGUAUAAUUGGCAUGUUAGUUACACAAAAAAAGGAUAAAUGCUUGAGGCAACGGAUAUACCAUUUACCUGAAUUUGGUUAUCACACAUUGUAUACUUGCAUUAAAAUGCCUGCCGGGCACAUGGCUCAUGCCUGUAAUCCCAGCACUUUGGGAGGCUGAGGCGGGCAGAUCACCUGAGGUCGGGAGUUUGAGACCAGCCUGACUAACAUGGAGAAACCCAUCUCUACUAAAAAUACAAAGUUAGCUGGGCAUGGCGGCUCAUUCCUGUAAUCCAAGCUACUCGGGAGGCUGAGGCAGGAGAAUCACUUGAACCUGGGAGGCGGAGGUUGCAGUGAGCCGAGACCGCACCAUUGCACUCCAGCCUGGGCAACAAGAGCAAAACUCCGUCUCAAAAAAAAAAAAAAAAACUUAUGUUCCCCAUAAAUAUAAAUACCUAUUAUGUACCAAUAAAAGUAAAAAGUAAAAAGUUUCAAUUGAUUCACAACUUUAAAAAAUAUCCACAGAGGCGUAAGAGGAGAUAUUGUAUUGCACCCACGAACCAGUCUUAUGCUAUUUCAGAAAGGGACAUUCAAGAAACAAAAAGGGAGCUCUUGGAAAUUUGAACAAUAAAUAAUAGUAGAAUAAAAAAUUCAGAGAAAGUUUGGAUGAUAAAUUUGAGCCAAUCUCCCAGUAAGCAGAGCAAAAAUAUAGAAAAUGAGAGUUAGAAAAGAAAAAGAAAAAAAUUAAAGGACUAAAAUAAGAAGUCCAACAUCUAAAUAAGAGGAGAUCCACAAAGAGCAACAGAGAUAAGAGAAGAAAGGAAAUAAUCAAUAAAAUAAUUCAAGAAAAUCCAAGGACAUGAGUUCUCAGAUUGUAAGAGACUACUUGAGUGAAAAAAAAAAAAAAAGAAUGGAGUUAGACCCAUCCCAAGGCACAUUAUUUGUGCGAUUUUAAAAUACCGAUAUAUUAGUUUGCUAGAGCUGCAGUAACAAAACACCACAGACUGGGUGGCUUGAACAGCAGAAAUUUGUUUUCUCAUGGUUCUGGAUGCUAGAAGUCUAAGAUCGAGGUGACAGCAGUUUCGUUUUUCCUGACGCUUCUCUCCUUAGCUCACAGAUGGCUGCCUUCUAGUUGUGUCCUCAUACUGUCUUCCCUUGGUCAGUGUUGUCUGUGUCCUCGUCUCCUCUUCUUAAAGGGACACCAGUCAUAUUAGGUUAAGAAUUGCCCAUUAGACCUCAUUUUACCUUAAUUACCUCUUUAAAGGCCCCACGUCUAAAUACAGUCAUAUUCUAAACUACUGGGGGUUAGGGCUUCACUGAGUGAAUUUUGGUGGAAAGUGGGGCAGGGGACACAAUUCAGCCUACAAAAACUGGAAACAAAGUGAAAAUCCUAUGUGUUUCCGUGCUCAGAAGACAGGAAGUACUCAUACCCAAGAGUCAAUAAUUAAACUGGUUUCUCACCAGCAAUUUGGGAGACUGGAAGUUGGAAGACACAGAGCAGUGCCUACCACAUUCAAAAGAGAAAAGAGGCCAGGCAUGGUGGCUCACGCCUGUAAUCCCAGAACUUUAGGAGGCGAGGAGGAUGGAUCACCAGGUCAGGUGUUCAAGACCAGCCUGACCAACAUGGUGAAACGCUGUCUCUACUAAAAAUACAAAAAUUAGCCAGGCGUGGUGGCGCAUGCCUGUAAUCCCAGCUACUCAGAAGGCUGAGACAGAAGAAUCACUUGAACCCAGGAGGUGGAGGUUGCAGUGAGCCGAGAUCAUGCCACUGCACUCCAUCCUGGGUGACAGAAUGAGACUCCGUCUCAAAAAAAAAAAAAAAAAAAAGAGAGAGAAAAGAAUUCCAACCCAGAAUUCUCAACUUCACUGUGUCAGAGGAUAUGAAGUAAACAAAUAUUCAUCUCUACAUUUGCCAGUCCCUGUGGACUUAGGCCAGAUAGUAUAAAUAAUAGUCACAAAAGGAGUAUGAAUGGGAUAAGAAGCCACUUCUAGUCUGAGACAAUUAAGAGUAGUAGUGCCUUCUCUGCACUCUCACCCCCUCAUUCUGACAGCUGAAGUGAAGGACUCCCAACUUCUGGAACUGCCCAAUGAAAGUAGCCUUGUGUGAGUGUUAGCUGGCCUGCUUUGGUCUGGGAUGCAAGUAGAAAUAAACUCCUCUCAUAUUAAGCCACUAAGACUUUAGGGAUAUGUUGCUGUAGCAUAGCCUAAUGUAGCCUGAUUACUGAACGAGCCACCCCAUCAACUGAAUCUAUGUAUAUACUAAAAACAUUUUAAGAUAUGCAAGGUCUCAAAGAGUUCACUCGAUGCACACUUUUUCUCAGGAAGCUACUAGAGGAUGUGCUCCACAAAAAAUAAAGGUAUAAAUUGUGAAAGAGGAAAACAUAGGAUUUAGGAAUCAAGGGAAUUCAGCACAAGACAGAAGAAAAGGGAAUCUGCAGCAAGAUCCCUGAGCUGUGCAUGUAACAUAAAGGGCAACAAUUUCCAACACAGAGCAGAUCACAAGACCCUAGGAUAGAUUUCUUGAAGAAAAUGAAAUUAAAAGAAUACUGGAUUCAUCUGAACAUAUGAAAAGGAGAUUUAAGCAACUUUUUAAGAGCUUGGGAAUGAAUUAAUGAUAAUAUAUAUGGUAUUAUGCAACCAAAACUACAAUAAAAACUCAUUAAAAAUUAUAACUCAUAAAAUUAUUAAUUUCAGGGAAAAUAAAAAGUUGAGUAGGAAUGAAAAAAGAAUCAGAGGAUACUAUAAAGCUCAUCUGUGGAUAUUGUUUACAUAGUCAUGAUAAUGAAAAAGAAAUAAUCUAACCAAAAUUAAACGUUGGAAGUGUGGGGAGAUAGAAAUGGUAGAGUGUAUUCGGUAUUUAUGUGUUGGGGAGGAUACCUGUAACUUUAACAUUAGUGAGCUUUACUUUACUAAGGCUAAAUAAACAAACUCAAGUGUCCAGAAAGGCUAGAGAAGAAGCUUACAAGAAUGAAGCUAUUGUGGUGUGAUUCAAUAGGGAAUAGGUGGGGCCUUGGCAACAUCAAUUUGUAGUAUCCCUGCCAAUUGAUACUACAACAUCAAUUUGUAGUAUCCCUGCCAAAAUUUAACUAUGGAAAAUAGUUAAAUUUUAAUAUGCACACAUCUGUGGUUGUGGUUAUACAGAUAUAUAUAUAUAUAUAUAUAUAUAUAAAAUAAAAAUUUAUAUAUAAAUAAAUACAUAAACAAACUCAAGUGUCCAACAGGGCUAGAUAAGGAGCUUACAAGAAUGAAGCAGUUGUGAUGUGAUUCAAUAGGGAAUAGGUGGGGCCUUGGCAAACCAAAAAACAUAUUCUAUCUAAAGUGGAUGGCCACAACUUGCUCCAGCUGUGGAAACUUGGGCCAUGUACUGCUAGAUCUAAGGAUUUUCUUUUGAGAGAUGCUAGAUAUAUACGUUUUUUAAAAAUAAAAUUAUCCUGAUUUUAACAACAUUGCCUUAUUAUAUAAAACAUACCUUGGAGGGUGUGGGUAAGACACAAUGUCCUUGAAAUUAUAUUUCACUAGGUUAAUAAAAUUGGCUCCGGAAGAAAAUAAUUUUAAACAGCAAACCAAAAAGUGAAGGCCUUCAAAACUAACAAACCAAAGGAAAACAAAACAAAAUGACAACAAGAAAAAAACAAAGAAACAAAACCCCUGGACCUUACCAUUUUUCUAAGGCAUGUUGACAUGAUAAAAUCAAAAUUGCUUUGUGCUUAUAAGGAUCAAAGGUUAUGCUUUUGACUUUAUAAAUUCAGAGAAAGAAUUUAAUUGGAAUUAUUUUUAUGAAUUAACUGAAGAUCUAAGGCAACUGGAUAAUUUAGGUUCUGCUAAUAUCUAGAAUAUUCAAAGUUUAUGUUUAGUCUGACACUAAAGAAUCCAUUAUUUCUCUUGACUUCCAGGCUGGUCAGUGUCUUUCCUGUGUCAUAUACCAAACAAUGUGUUAGAAAUUGUCUUCUCACUCAUAAACUAAUAUUUGUUCAGAGUAAAAAGUCAAGCAAGUAAAUAAUGAGAAAAAAUUCAGUGUAUUGUAUAAACAAAGACAGAAGGCAGACCAAUGGUUACCUGGGGCCUAAGCUAAAGAGAUUAAUUGUACACAGACACAAAGGAAUUUUUUGGGAUGGUGAAAGUGUUCUAAAACUGGAUUGGGAUGAUUGUGGCACAACUGUAUAAAUGUUAUUAAAACUCAUUGAGUUGUACACUUAAAUGAGUGGCUAAGUUGUGCUUUAAUAAAGCUGUAAUUUUGAAAAAGAAUAAUGGAUGAUCAACUGUGGGCUAGAGUAUGAUGAAAACACAAGACAUUUACAUAGUUUCAAAGUAUCUCCCCAUCAGGUACUUAUUAACUGCAUCAGGGAAACAGUAAUUUUCUUGUGGCAGAACCCUGCUGACAAAGUUAACAUUCUAGUAAAAGCACAGGUGGAUGUCAUGUGCCUCCUGAAGUGAUGCACAGAGAAGGAUGCAACAUCAACUUGUAGUAUCCCUGCCAAAAAUAUAAAACCUGAAUUUAACCAUGCUGAAACAUAAGACAAAUCCAAGUGAAGGAACAUUCUACAAAACAACUGACCAGUACUCCUCAAGAGUGUCAAGGUCCUGGAAGACAAAGACUGAGCAAUGCUUCUGAUUAAAGUAGACUGAGAGGUGACAACUGAAUGCAAUGUGGGAUUCUGGAUUAGGUCUUGGCCCAGAAACAGGUCUUCGGUGGGACAACUGGCAAAAUGUGAAUAAGGUCUCUGGUUUUGUGAAUGGUAGCGUAUCGACGCUCAUUACCUGCUUUUGAUCAUGGUAGUGAUAGUAAGAUAUUAACAUUCAGGAAAGCACAGUGAAGGGUAUAUGGGAACCUCUACUAUUUUUGUAGCUUUUGUAAGUUGAAAUUGUUUCAAAAUGAGUUAGAAAAUUAAAAGGAAGUUUUCUCUUUCAGCUGGGAAAACGGCAAUGGAUUAAUAACAAGAAAUUAAUGGUGAAGUGGUGACGAAAAUUCUACAUUGCUUAGAAAGCAAAUAGUGAAAUGAACAUUUACAUUCUGGCAACCUCAGAAGUACAACGAACAAAGGACACCAGCCAGGUAGGGCAAAGGCCUGUGAACCCCCUUUUGCUGUUAAAUGUUUAUCAGAUGAGUGCUCUGUUUCUGUUAUAUUAUAUUGCUUUUCUCUCCAAUGUUUACUGAGGAAGAACAAGUAGCUCCUCAGGCAAGUCAACUGUUAACUUUGCAGUUUUUAUUUAAUCUCCCAGGAAUGUAACCCUUAACUUUAAAGAAUGUAGUGACCAUAAAACUUAUAAAGCAUGUUUCUUAAGGAAAUUGUACCUGUUUAUUUAAUCUAUCAGAUAUGAAUGUUAUAGAAAAUUAAAUUUGUCCACUUAAGCUGUAGAUGAACUUUUCACCUUUCUGAUCAGAAAUUCACCAUCUUAUAGUAUAGGUUCUGUUAUUAAUCAGAAUAUUUCAUUUAGACUCUUUCUAUCCAACUUUUUCUUAGAGGCUAUUCAAAAUAAAGGUGCUUCUAACAGUUUCAUAUCGAAAUACGAUGCAAAGCCUUGCUCUUCCAUGGUAUCCUUUGAGUGAGCCAAACUUAUUUAGCCAUUCCCCUAUAGUUAAAUAGCUAGGAUGUUUCCAACAUCUCACCUUUAAAACAAUAGUGCUAUGAAUGUCAUAAAUGUUUGUAUAUGUAAAUAUGUAGGAUAAAUCCCUAUCAGUAGAAUUUCAAAAGGUAUACGCAAUCAGUAUUUUCAUACAUAUUUAAAAUUUUCCAUCCAUACAAAGGUUGCUAACAUAUUUAUUUAAAAUUUUAAAAAUAAUUUUAUAUGCCUCUUGUAACCAGUAAUAGGAUGCAAAGUUUUUUUUAAGGUAACAUUGCUCCUCUUCCCCCAUUGUCUCUGUCAUCUAUAGUACUCCCUGAGGUAGUUCAUGUUAUUGCAAGGGUGUGUAUCAUCACAAACAUAUUGCUUCCACAUACAUAUAUCAGCAUACAUAUAUAUAUAUGUAUAGCAUAUAUAUAUAUGAGCACAUAUUAAUAUAUGCCCAUGCACAUACAAGCAUGUUUUUGUUAAUUUUUACUGAAAUGGAAUCAUACUGCAUACUUAUGAACAAAUUGCUUCUUUCACCUUAUAUCACUUAUAAUUGUUAUUCUACAAAUCAGUACAUAUAAAAAAUACAUAUUUACAUAUGUAAUACUCUAUCUUUCUGUUAUAAUUUUCUGCAUGCACAUGUAUGCAUAUACAUAUAUUCAUAAACAUAAAACUUAAUCUAAACGGGAUUUUUUUUGGGGGGGGUGAUAUGGUUUGGCUGUGUCCCCACCCAAAUCUCAUCUUGAAUUCCCAUGUGUUGUGGGGGGACCCGGUGGGAGGUAAUUGAAUUAUGGGGGCAGGUCUUUCCUGUGCUGUUCUCGGGAUAGUGAAAAAGUCUCACAAGAUCUGAUGGUUUUAAAAAGAUGAGUUUCCCUGCAUAAUCUCUCUUCUCCUGUCUGGUUCCAUGUGAGAUGUGCCUUUUGCCUUCCGCCAUGAUUGUGAGGCCUCCCCAGCCAUGUGGAACUGCCCAUAGGUGGAAGGGACUUGCCUUGUCUCAGAUGAGACUUUGGACUUUGGACUGUGGACUUUUGAGUUAACACUGAAAUGAAUUAAUGCUGAAAUGAAUUAAGACUUUGGGAGACGGUUGAGAAGCCAUGACUCAUUUUAAAAUGUGAGAACAUGAGAUUUGGGAGGGGCUGGGGUGGAAUGGUAUGGUUUGGCUGUGUCCCCACCCAAAUCUUAUCUUGGAUUCCCAUGUAUUGUGGGAGGGACCCGGUGGGAGGUAACUGAAUCAUGGGGGCAGGCCUUUCUCAUGCUGUUUUUGUGAUAGUGAAUAAGUCUCAUGAGAUCUGAUGGUUUUGAAAAGGGGAGUUUCCCUGCACAAGCUCUCUUCUCUUGUCUGCUUCCAGGUGAGACAUGCCUUUCACCUUCUGCCAUGAUUGUGAGGCCUCUCCAGCCAUGUGGAACUGUGAACACACAGUGUUCAUCCCCUCAGGAGGACACAGCUUUUGAGGUACCAUCUUGGAAGCAGAGACCAGCCCUCACUAGACACAAACUUCCUGGCACGUUGAUUUUGGACUUCAUAGCCUCUAGAACUGUGCUGGGAAGACAACACUUCUGAACUAUAUUUUGACAGAGCAACAUAGUAAAAGAGUAGCGGUCAUUUUAAAUGAAUCUGGGGAAGGAAGUGCGCUGGAGAAAUCCUUAGCUGUCAGCCAAGGUGGAGAGCUCUAUGAAGAGUGGCUGGAACUUAGAAACGGUUGCCUCUGCUGUUCAGUGAAGGACAAUGGCCUUAGAGCUAUUGAGAAUUUGAUGCAAAAGAAGGGGAAAUUUGAUGACAUACUGUUAGAGACCACUGGAUUAGCAGACCCUGGUGCAGUGACUUCUAUGUUUUGGGUUGAUGCUGAAUUAGGGAGUGAUAUUUACCUUGAUGGUAUCAUAACUAUUGUGGAUUCAAAAUAUGGAUUAAAACAUUUAACAGAAGAGAAACCUGAUGGCCUUAUCAAUGAAGCUACUAGGCAAGUUGCUUUGGCAGAUAUCAUUCUCAUUAAUAAAACAGACUUGGUUCCAGAAGAAGAUGUAAAGAAAUUAAGAACGACAAUUAGAUCCAUAAAUGGACUAGGACAAAUCUUAGAAACACAAAGAUCAAGAGUUGAUCUCUCUAAUGUAUUAGAUCUUCAUGCCUUUGAUAGUCUCUCUGGAAUAAGUUUGCAGAAAAAACUUCAGCAUGUGCCAGGAACACAACCUCACCUUGAUCAGAGUAUUGUUACAAUCACAUUUGAAGUACCAGGAAAUGCAAAGGAAGAACAUCUUAAUAUGUUUAUUCAGAAUCUCCUGUGGGAAAAGAAUGUGAGAAACAAGGACAAUCACUGCAUGGAGGUCAUAAGGCUGAAGGGAUUGGUGUCAAUCAAAGACAAAUCACAACAAGUGAUUGUCCAGGGUGUCCAUGAGCUCUAUGAUCUGGAGGAGACUCCAGUGAGCUGGAAGGAUGACACUGAGAGAACAAAUCGAUUGGUCCUCAUUGGCAGAAAUUUAGAUAAGGAUAUCCUUAAACAGCUGUUUAUAGCUACUGUGACAGAAACAGAAAAGCAGUGGACAACACAUUUCAAAGAAGAUCAAGUUUGUACAUAACACUAGUGGCAUUUCUUAUCAAAAGGAUUGGAUAAUAAAAAUAAGUUUCUACUGGGUAUAUUUCAAGCAUUUAUUUAUUACUUUAGUUACGAAUUCCAAUAUACUUUAAAAUGGUAUUUGUUUUACAGCAUACAUAAAAUGUAGCAAAUCAGUACUGUAAAACAUUUAACAUUCAUACAAUUAUAUAUAAUAUCCUUUUUUUUAAAGAAUGGUAUUUCACAAAAAUAUCUUUUGAAAUUGGCUUUGGAGUUUACAUAUACUGAACAUGAAAGUUUAUAAUAAUGAUGAUACAACUUUCAACAUCGUCAUUUUUUCUUAGAACUUCAGCUGAUUGCAGAGAUAUAAUGAUUACAUUGUUAUUAAAUUUUUUUAACACAAGUAAGUGUCACCAUUUUAUGACAUGAAAUAAAAGGUUAUGACUGUUA